AGAGAAGGGUGUCCCAGAUGUAGGCAAAGCGUCCUCCAUGUGUUCCUGGAGGACCGUCCCAAGUCCUUCUCCAUUCUCCCAACCUCUUGGGCCUGGAAGUCAGACAAGUACCGGUGAUUGCCGGUUUCUUGUCUGAUUUUUGCACUUCUCUGGCAAGCUGCCCCCUCUGAAGAGUUGACUAUUUGGGAGUUACUCACUGAUGGUUCAGCCACUUCCAGAACCUACCCCAAGAGCAAGACUUGAAACCAACUCGCACCCUCAAAGCUCCGGAAGCCAUUCAGUGUUUCCAUCUUGGCUGAGUGAGUUCUUCACUGAAACUCAAUUUGACUUUGACAGUCAUCUAAUGAGAACUCAAAAGUCAUUCUUGGUUCAGCCACAGUCAAAGAACUUGCAGAGCAUUCUCUGACGAGGUCCUCAAGGACAACUGAGAGAAGGUCCCAUUCCAGGUCUUGCCCAAGUCUUUCUGAUUGGUGGGACUUAAAUCACACCCAAAAUUCCAGCUGCAGGAGAGCUCUGAGAUUUCAUCUUUCCAACCUCUGUGUGCUACGUGGGGGUUGGAGCACUUGCUGACAAGCCUUGCAACCACCAUUGACAGGAUGUCCUCCACCUUUUCAAUCUGAUUUGCUCUUUGCCAUGCAGACCUGUGGAUGAAGAGCCAGAGUCCUCCAAGGUGAAGCUGGACUGAAUAUUUCUGUCCAUAAGACUAUUAGAAUCCCCCAAAGUGGGAUACCAGUGAGGACCUCACCAGCAGCUGCUGUCUCUCCAAUGCAGCUCCACAGGGCCUGUGAGCAGGGCUGGCUAUGAGAUCCUGCCCUGAAGAGCAGUACUGGGCUGCUCUGCUAGGCACCUGCAUGUCCUGCAAAGCCAUCUGCAACCAUCAGAGCCAGCGCACCUGUGCAGCCUCCUGCGGUGAUCUCAGGGCCUGUCCCUCUCCAUGGGGCCUCUCCACCUGGACGACUUGAGUGGUGCUCAAAGCUCCCAAGGGAGCAAACACCGAGGCUGUCAGGCCUUCUUGAGGCGGAGGCCCAGAGUGGCACAGCCUCACCCCCACGGCACUCUCCUGGAAUGAGUCCCAGAUAGUCCACAAGGGUGUGAUGUUGGGUGACCGUGCUCUGGGCGUGGUGGAUCAGCUGCUGGACGGUGAGAGGCACUCCCUGCAGGGUAGGUGGACGGCUGCCCCCAGGGCCUUACACAGCAAGGCCAGGGGACGGCCACCCUGGCCGGUGAGCCCGACUUCCAGGCAAGGCGCCUUCCUUGCAUCCCAGCUUGUUUGGAGCCUCCAGGACAUCCCUACUGAGGGUCCCACAGGAGCCUGGGUCUGGACAGGGACCCUCUCACCUCAAGUCAGACACCUUUCAUCCCCAACAGCAGAGGGACUGAUACCUCCCCCUGGCUACCCUCUGUCGCCCGAAGCCAGCCCUGACUUUGUGCAGGCGCCACUCACCUUCCUGAGGGUCCACCUGCCUCCCAGCUGGCUGUGCUCCCAGCCACCCUCCCUGCACAUGAAUGGGCCAACGAAGUCCAGAUAGCAAUGUCUGCCCAUCACAUAUCCCCCAGCCUGACCCCAUAUCCAGCAUCCCAGCACCCACCCUGUUCUGCUGGCACCCACCUGCCUCAGCCCUGCUUCGUGGUGUCAGAGGCAGGCCUAUCCUCCUGGCACCUCGACCCAGGAAGCUGCUGGGCAGCGCCUCCAGCCAGGGCCCUCCUCCCCUGGGCUGAGGCUGUGUGGUGGGGUCACUGGAUGGGAGGGAGGGAGGCCUUGGGGCCCGGAGUACCCUGCCACUACCCAGCAAUUCCAGCUGAUGCCUCCACAUCUUUGGAGUUGGGUCUGAUUGGUGAUGGGUUGGGGGCUUCUCAGUGUUCUACAGUCCAAUACUGCCCAGCUCCGGAGGCUCCUAUUGUACCAGGAGCAGGUGUUGCAUAAGUGCUUUCUGAAGAUCAUGAGACACCUGGUGAGUGAACGAAACCCUGGGUCCCAUGGGCCAGGGGAGACUCGAGCCCCUCCUGGGGCUGGCAAGAGGCCGCGUCCCAGCCAUGGCCUGACCUGGGAUGGGGAUUCUCCAUGAGUUGGAAGUUGGGUUUCCUUUUCUUGCCCCAGAGGAUCCAGAGACGCUGGGACCAGGGCUGAGCUCUGGCUAAGCAGGGCUAAGGGAGUGUGUCCACCGGGCGUCGUGCACGGACGUGUUGGGAGACCCCUGGCCACCACCCAGGGUUCUGCUCCUUGAGGAAGGGUCUGCAGAGGGGCCUGAAAAGGGGGAUUGCAGGGCAGCUCAGGAGGCCCUGAGUACCUCUGCCUCUCCCUGCAGGGCAAGGAAGGACUGUGCAUUGAGUGUUUCAUGCUGCGGUGGCUCCUCCAGUGUUUCAUUGAUGGGAAGCAACAGCGCUGCUGAGGUGGGUCCCCCAUGAGGAGCUGCAGGACCUUGUCUGACCCUGCUUUAUAGGGGGCUCUCAUCCCAUGGAGAGGUGUUCCCAGCAUUCCAGGAGACUGAAACCCCAGGCGGCCCUGCUCAGGCCUCUGAGCCCAGCCCAGAAAGGCAGGUCCUCCCACACUUCCUGUCCCCACAAAAUCCUUCGGGCUCACCCUGCAACUGUGGGAUAUGCUCAUCUUGGAGGGCGAGCAGGUACUGUUGGGCAUGGCGCAUGCAUCAUUCAAAAUACAUGGGUAAGUCCUGUGUGCCCGAGGGUGCCAGGGGGAAUACACAGGACAGACCCCGGCUGGCCUGAGGGAAGUGUCCUUACACUGUCCCUAUGACUCUCUGCUCUGUCUUGAAGGGGGUUCUGGUCUGGUGGGCUGGGCAAGGCACGAUGACACUGAGCCCACCCCCCACAUGACCCAGAUGAAAGUCAGGAGUGUGGUGAGCACUUCCCUGCCUGGCCUUCCCCAGCUGUGGCCUCCUGUGCACAGCUGGACCCCAGGGUGGCCAAGAAGGACCACACACCACCCAGUGGGAGGUGGGCCUGGUGGAAAUGGGGUGCAGGCACUGAUCCCCCCACAAGGGAAUCCUCCUGGCCUGAUACCCGCCCUGUCCCUAGAGUGCCUCAUGAAGCUUUCCUGGAGCACCAUCUGGGAGUUUCAGGAGCGACUUUUUCAGAGCUGGGCCCCGGAGGACAACGUGGUCCUCAGGAACCUUCAAACCUCCGUGAAGGAACUCACAAGGAAACACUGGGACCUGCCACCCCCAGGAGGACAGGGGCACUGCAGAUCUCCAGGUGACCACGCAGGGCACCAGGGCACUGCAAGCCCUGAUGCUGUAAGGAUUCACAUCAGAGAACCUGGGCAAGCCAGGCCAGAGACGCUGAGCCCGUGCAGUGAUGAGGAUGUGGAGGGCUGGCUCAAGGGGGUCAACAGCUGUGAACACUGCUGCCUCUUCCCGGCCUCAUUGUUGCAGUGCAGGCAGUCUGCACCCCGGAGCCUGGCCCAACAGCGCCCCGAGUGCCCUAGUCCACUAUGCCAACAUGGUACCCGGAGGCUUCGAGGCCCUGCCUGCUGCACCACCCGCCUCCUGGAGGCCUUGUUCUGCAGCCUAGCCCCUGCCGCAGCCACAGCAGGCACCACUGCCAAGUGCCUUCCAGCCGGGCUUCCCAGAGGACAGAGGCAUCCUGCAGUCAUUGCCUCAGCAGCUCACACUGUGAAGAUAGUUUCAUCCACAUUCCCAUGUUCCCACCAAAGAGAAUCCCUGCAGAGGGUGCUCUUGAUCCUGCGGUGGGGAAAACAGCACACUAGGUGGACUCAGCUCCUUUCCCUGGCCACCAUGAUUGCUGGAUGGGCCCACAAAGCAGCCAUCAGACAGGCAUGUUGGGGAAGAGCCUAAGCAAUCCUGCUUGUUCCCUGACCAGACCGACACCACUGCCGAGUGCCCCAUCUGCUGAUGAGAGAUUUGGUGUCGAUCCCUGGACUGGCACCAUUUCCCAGGAGGAGCGGCUGGCUACCUGUGGGCAGGCUGCCCACACUGUGGAGAGGGCUGAGAUCGGCCUUCACUACGGGGAGCCCCUACCUGGACAUAGACUCGCCAGCCCUGCCUGUUGCCAUCACAGCAGCCCACAUGGCAUUGCUUGUGACCAGGGUACCCCAUUCACAGUGACGGACAUGCAGCAGUGGCCCUUGACUAGGGAACUAACUCUUCUCGCUACGUCACCCACCGCCUGGAAGCAACUGGACUUAGGAUCGCUGUUAUGCUGAAGUGGUGAGGUUGUCUUACAAGAUGAAUUUUAUCCUUUCUACUGGAAGCCAGUGUAUGGUGAUGACUCCCCCACAACCAGAAGGUGUAGUUCUGAGUGAAGGUGUGAAAGUGGACGAUGUUCAGUGUUGCACCGAAUGUCUCAGUCACAAAGUUUUCCUAUUGCCUGUCCUGGAGAAAUGGAACUUUGCUGGUUGGAAGGUCUUAGGACCCAGGAAGAGUGAAGCUUCCCCCAGGGGAACACAACAAUGGUUCUAUUUAAUAUGAGGAGACAGGACUAAGUCUGAAACCUCGGGGCAUUCUCUGGUGUUCUUGAGUGUUUCCAUGUAAAGGAAGUCAAGUAACUUGCCACAAAGCUUUGCCACAGAAGCAUCUGAAAAAGGAGGGGGCAGAACUAUUCAGAACUCAGAGGUUUCAGAACCAAAGAUGAGGCCGAGAAGAUUCCUGACCCGCUGAGGGCAAGGGAAGUAUGUGGGGGCGGCUGGGAGAGGAUGUUAUAGAGUCCGCCAUGGCCUCGUGACCUGUCACAGAACCGUGCACUUUAAUAGCUGUGCACAUCUUCUCUGCACUGAUUAUAGUAUUUCUUUGCCUUUGCUACUCUCCACACAGGGAGCUUGCUACAAAAUGCACAUAACCACAGCCCGGGUCUUGCAAUCCAAGCCUGGCAAGGAUUCAGCAUGUCAAGGGCUUCAGGUCUGAAGGUCCAUGGCUGUCCUGAAUCCUGGAUAUCACCUUCUUGCCCAAAAAAGGAGGGACGAGGCUCAAACCGCAGCAGGCCACUCACAGAAAGGGACGAAACGUUGAGUGCGUGGCCUCCCUGACACCCAGACAAGACUUUGGGCCCAAAGCCAGGCUGCAGCUCUGGCCACUGACUCAGACCAGGGACGCCCCCAUGCAGGCCGGUGUCCCCUGGCCGCUCUUCUCCCUCCUGCCACCCUCUCUUCGGCUGCUUGUGUCAAUAAAAGGAAAACUGGCCAGUUCUCAGAGAAAAUGUAGCUUUAUUAUGACAUAGGAGAGACUACAAAGCACUGGGGGGGAGGAGGAGUGACACAGCUCCUCAAAAUGGAAGGGGAAAGGAAGAGUAAACAUCUUGGUAAAUAAAGUCUCCAACCACAGCACAGUCAUUGGAAUUUUUUUCUUCAUUUUUAUUUUCAAACUUACAGUAAACAAAA